AUUUAGGAGACACGGGGAAGAGACAGAGAGGAGGGUAAAGUGAGAAUCCUGCCCGCACCACAGGUCUGGACUGCUAACCUUGAAUCCUGGUUUCUUAAAUUCUGCCUCCGCUUCUGACUGAGGACCACUGGAUUUUGAGGAAACUUUGGUCUUGUGGUGGUGAGGAGGUGAUGUUCUGGAAGGAAGGUACCUAGACUUUGUGGUCCCUGCCAGGAAGUGGAGAGUGGAAAUGUGGAAUGCCUCACACUCCUCAACUAGAAUUCCCGUACUGAUUAGUCAACAGUGGAAAAUCUGAAGAGAUGCAAGCAGGAAAAAGAAAUUAAACCAGUAAGAUAGAGACUGCCACUCUCUGGGAACCUUGCUGUGUAGCUGAGCCUCAGCAAGUUUGAUAAUACAGACACAGCAGGAGGCCUGGGGAGGACCCAGCAUGCCCGGCCACCAAGCAGUGAUGCAGCUGGACUGUUCCGCAGCUUUCCAGAGACCUCCAUGGAAGCACAGACUUCCAUGGGUUGAAGAGAGUUUGUGUCACAAUUCCAGUCCCUAGCCCUGGCCCUGUGUGAAGUAGUAACACCGCCCUGCCAGUAGGAUAUAGCUGCUGAGGAGGCCUGAGGAGCGAUGCGACAGGCAUGAUGGAGGUCGAGUCCUCCUACUCGGACUUCAUCUCCUGUGACCGGACAGGCCGUCGGAAUGCGGUCCCUGACAUCCAGGGAGACUCAGAGGCUGUGAGCGUGAGGAAGCUGGCUGGAGACAUGGGCGAGCUGGCACUCGAGGGGGCAGAAGGACAGGUGGAGGGAAGCGCCCCAGACAAGGAAGCUGGCAACCAGCCCCAGAGCAGCGAUGGGACCACCUCGUCUUGAAUCUGACCUUGUCCAAGAAGGCUGGACGAGAGACCUUCUGUCCCCUCCCAGAGGGGGAACCCUGGCACUGGCCCAGCAGCCUCUUCUCUGAGCUCCAUGUCCCAGAUAAACCAGGCCAGACUGAGAAGGCUCCCCAGAGGCCUCUGUGGCCUCCACUCCGGGAAAGCCCUCUGCCCACACCCACAGGCUUCACAUUCCCACCACCUUCGCACCGUGCCCAGGUACACUUUCAAGACACUGUAACCACAAGAUGUUAUUUAUUGAGCUGGCGCCGGGACUUGGGCGGGGCCUGCCCUACAGUGAGCAGCCCACACAGGAACGCUCCUCUCGCGAGCGGCCCGGGCAGGGACCCUGUCCCAACACCAACACCUCCUCUCCAGCCCAAUCUUCUGGGUCCAGACCUGCUUGUCCCUUUUUUAGAAAACACUUUUAAACUUUUUAAAAAUUUUAAACCUUUUUUCAGCAGAUAUGGAGAGAGCUGACAAUCAAUUCACAUUUUUUAAGCCAUUUUAGCUAAACUGUCAUUGUGCAUCUCUGAGGUUCCCUCAUGGAGCUCCACAGAUCCAUUUUUAGGGAAGGGAUUUUGGCUCAAAACGAUCUGACCACCUCUGCCCUGUCCACCAGGAUAAGUGACACCUAGGACCCAGGAAAUAAAUGCCGAUGAUUUGUGUGA